CCCGUCCGUCCCCACUCCCAACCCCCACCCUGGGAGCCUGAAGAAACACAUUGGACCAUUAUGCAACAGCCCCAUCCCCUGGGCAGAAAGCAUUUAUUAAGUGCCACAGUAUGCUUGGCCCAUGUUAGUAUCCAGCAGGGCCACAGAUGAAGGUGCCAUGAUCCCAAGAAGUGAGAAUCCAUUUGGGCAGGCGGGAGGCCUGGUUAGAGCUGUGGUGAGCAGUGACUACAGGAUCUGGUACAGGUCCUCUUCAAAUUUACCCUGCCCACCACAUCCCGUUGCUCCUUCCCCUACUACCCCUGUUGUCCUGGGCUGGAGAGGGGUGAAUAUGGAAUAAGAGGGUGAGCUUUCCUCGGGGCACUGAGCCAGGAAAGUCUUGAAGCCCCAUGCAAGGCAGUGGGUCAUAUACUGGGAGGUAGUCUAUUCUAGGAGAGAGGGCAGACAGGGAGAGCCAGUGUCCUGGGGAGGGAAUACUUGGAGGAAUUGUCCUAGGUGGCAGGGGUUGGAGGACUGCAGGAACUGAGACAUGAAAAGGUGCCAUUCUAGGCAAGGUUCAAUGGAUGGCCAAACUCUCCCCCAGGGCCUAGUUCACCUAGGUCCCAGGGACCCUAUGGGGUCAAAGUCCACCAUCACCCAGAGUGUGGCUUACUGCCCCACCCGGAAAAGGCCACAUCCUCUUUAAUCCCUCUUCUCUCCUAGGCUGACCUAGGACCUCCUUCCUCCAGGAAGCCCUCCCUAACUGCCAUGUUGUGUGCCAUGACAUGCAUAAAACAGCCAGGAGGGUUUCUGAACCCCUGGCUCCCAGAGCCUCUUUAGCGCCUGAUGUCUUCCACAAGAUGGUGAGUUGCCUGACGGCAGGUACGGGGCCUGCUAACUACUUCCUGGAUUCUAAGUGAUCACUGCUAUGGAUGAUCGAUCCAUCCUUCCAUUCAGCCAUCCAUCCAAAAACUUCUGAGCACCGCAGGUUGCCAGUUCUGUGCCAGGCCCUAGGGAUAAGCAACAAAGCCCUGUAUAGCCCUGUCUUAAAAAGCGAUAUUGAAUAGUUCUUUCUCAAUAAGACAUUCCUCUCUCAGUGUGUCUGAGGCUGUCUCCCCAGGCCACAUAGGAUUUAGUGCAGGCGUAUUCCUCUGUGAAGCUGCAGGUGACCCCCACAUGAACACCAGGCCUUGGUGUGCUCCACCUUCUGCUGCAUUUGUGACGCCGCUUGUCUCUCACCUCUGGUCUCAAGGCCAUAAGCUCUUCAUGGCAUCCUUAGAACUUAGAGACACCUGGCCAGGUGCGGUGGCUCACGCUUGUAAUCCCAGCACUUUGGGAGGCCAAGGUGGUUGAAUCAGCUGAGGUCAGGAGUUCGAGACCAGCAUGGCCAACAUGGUGAAACCCCAUCUCUACUAAAAAUACAAAAAUUAGCCGAGCGUGGUGGCAGGUGCCUGUAAUCCCAGCUACUGGGUAGGCUGAGGUAGGAGAAUUGCUUGAACCUGGGAGGCAGAGGUUGCAGUGAGCCGAGAUCGUGCCACUGCCCUCCAGCCUAGGCAAUAAAAGCAAGGCUCCAUCUCAAAAAAAAAAAAAAAAAAAAAAGAACUUAGAGGCAUCUGCAGCUUCCAGGUGAAUUUGGGCCCAAAGAAGGCAGAGGACUGACUUGACUUCACUCGGCAAGCCAGUGUUGGGUCAGGGACUAGGACACAGGCUGGCACUCCCGACCCCUUGGACAACUGGUACACCCGGCAGCCUAGGACCUGGCACACAGUGGCCACUCCACGUUUGCCUUCGCUGUCGCCACCUUGGUGUCUCUGACUCUAGACUCCUUCCUGGGGAAAUUCAAGCCUAAUGUUUCCUUCUGGUGAGGGAACCCCAAACCCAUUCAUCAGGAACAAUGGCUGGCACAAUGUGGGAAAAAUAACCCAUGGGAAUAGUCCUAACAAGCCCUGUGAAGCUCUGGGGCAGCUCUUCUCAUAAUUUGCCCAUCACCUCUCAAGCCAAUUUGGCCAAGUUUCCUUAGGAUUUCAUCAGGAAAUAUGAACUGCCAAUUUUGUUAUUAAGUCUUUAUUUUAAUAACAAUUCUUGGUUAUUGUAUGAAGUCCGAGGGAUGGAGCAGGAGGGGAGAACCCACAGAAGAGUCCUUCCUUCCUUAUGAAGAAAGAACUGACCCCAAAGCCCCCUUGCUUCAUUUUAAGGGCAGCUGCCUGGUACCUGAUGCAGAGUAGCAGCAUCCCAGCAAUUGUGUGUGCUUGCCUUUCUGUAGGUCACAACCACCUACAUGCACACACAUGGACACACACGCCCCAACAAACAGUGAAACUACACAGAGUUUCCAGAAAGCAAACCGUGUUUCUAGUAACAAACCACAGUCUACCUCUAGGACCUGUAACCGGGUUUUGCCCUGAGAGGAUGCUCCAUGGGAAGUGCUCCUGCCGAGAGCCAGCAGCCCAGCCUCCCGGCGGCUUUGGGCAAGCCCCAACAGGAUGCCAGGCGGGCUGGUGAGCAGGAAGAGACGCCGCUCACAACCUCUCCUUGCUGUAAUUUACUAAAUCCAUCUGGGGCUCCUUUGAGACGUUUUCUGGAAAUGCCACAUUUCAAGGGUCUCCCUGUCAGAAAAGGUCAGAGUUCACGUGGGCCUUUCAUGUUAAAGGAGCUUGAAAGAAAAGGAAAGGAAAUGUAUAUUUUCAGCUCUAGCCAUGAUUAAGUGGGCUCAGGCCAUGAGAACAUUCAGAUGAUUUACAUGACGUUACAUGAAGAGCCAAUUAGCCUAACAACUUCCGAAAAAUAUCUCGUUCAAGAGCACCCAUUAGACACUUGGAAUGCACCAGGCUGCUGUUCUAAGCUCUUCACUAGGGUACAGUGGUUCAUCUCGACUGCACUCCAACAGAGCAGGGCAGGCCUGCGUAUGACAUCCAUUUAACCUAUGGGGAGACUGAGGCUCAGAGAGGGUCAGCAAUCUGCCUGGGGUCCCACAGCUAGUAAGUGGCACGGCAGAGAUGGAAACUUAAGACUGCCCAAAUCUAAAGCUGGAGCUCAUCUGCUCCAACAACCCUCAAGCCUUGGGAGUCCUGACUUAGUCCUGUUUCCAGCAUCUGACUAGUGCAAGCUCAUUUGCGUGAAGAUGAAGCCUUAUUAAAUCACCAGCCCUGGCCUGGUCUGGAUGAAUCCAGAAGACUCUGGGGCCUCCUUGCAGCUGGUCCUGGUCCUGAAACUCCCCGGUCACCUCCAGGGGGGCAACCACAGCAGAUUGCACUCACUACCCUGUGGAAGAACCCCAGUGUCUAUCAUCUGUGUAUGUGAUCUGAGCCAAUUCCCAGAACAGGUGGCCUCGGGUGGGCUCAGCAGAGAGAUGGUACACACUGAGAUCUGUCUGGUUCAAGGGAGAGAUUCUAGGCCCUCUCUGCCAGCAAAGGUCUUGGGCCCCCUAUACAGACCACCAAGAUGAUUCCCUAAUCCUGUUGAUGGCCCCCUUCAUGCAACAUGAGCCACCCAGAAAGUCAGGGCUCCAUAUUAGUGACAGCUUAUUUGUCAGCAUUUGUCUGCCAAGACCACAAGGCAAAUAAGGACUCCCUCUGGAAUUUUAUAAUGGAACACUAGAGUGUGAUAGUUAGGAUGUGGGCUCAGGAGUCAGACUGCCUGGGUUUCAAAUUCUGACACCUUCAUUUUCAAGCUGUGAGAACUUAGGUGACUUCAUCUCUCUGAGCUUCAGUUUCCUCAUUAGUCAAAUGGGGAUACGAGUCCCUAUGUCACAGGGUUGGUGUGAUGAUUAAAUGAGAUAAUGUGUGUGAAGCUCUUGACAGGAUGCCUGGCACAUAGUAAUCACUCAGUAUAUGAGGUUGGUCGUUGUGUAGACGAUGGUGAAGGAAUCAGUGCUGACUAGACCAGGGACUCCUGUGGGGCCGCACCAACUUCUGGGGAACAAAUCAGAGCUCUUGUUCCUUUCCAGCUUUCCAAACCCUCCUAAGCCAUCCAGGCCCACAUGAAAUCUACCUCCUUCAGGAAGCCACCCUGACUACUCUAGUCCACAUUGAUCUCACCAUAUCUGAGCUCUUUCUGUCCAUUACCUGUAUAGACUACUCUAGCACCUAAAUCGGCUCUAAUAACUCUUCAGCUUCUCAAAGCAGCCAAUGGCUCCUGGAAGGCAGACACCUCUAGCCCUUCCCUCUCCACAGCCCAAGCCAGGGCUAGGUACACAGUAGAUGAUCCCUUAGCAAGCCUUCAGACUGAUUUCAGUGUGGCUGUGGAUGCCUGUGACUCAGCCCUUCUCUCCCUCACGCCUCCUCACAGUCCCACUCUCCCUACUCACCCACCCUCUCCUCUGGUUCCAGCCAGCAGGGUGGGGAGUUGGAGCUAUGACCCCAUAGGACAGUUGUUCCCAGACUAUAAAAUGUCCAAAGAAACUUGAGGGUGGGGGAGUUAACAGAUGGGGAAAAAAAUGUUCCUUAUGUUCUUUCACCAAAUAAAGACAUGAAAAAAAACACUUGUCCCACCACCAUUUUAGUAAAGAAAGGAUGUUUUCACACCAAUAAAGCAGUAAGGGCAUAAUCCUUGAUUAAAGGCUAAUACGAAGCUGGAAAGUUUUAACCUUAUUGAGAAAACAAAACAAAACAAAAAGAACCUCACUGUUGUUGUGACUUUUCUCCUUUCUCCAAGGACUGGAGAACACUUCAGCCUCCACUGAUCUGUGUCGGUGGAACUCAUGGGUCUGGGGACAGCUAUUCUGGAGGACGUUCCUGCUGAACCAGGGUUCCCUACAAACACAUGAGGACCCCUAAAGCCAUUGGGUUGGGCAGAUCCGGAUUCCCUUUCAGCUGUCCCAGAGGAGGCUCACCCUAUGCCAGACCCUACCUAUAACCUCAGGAGUUGAGGUGGCGGAGGCUCUGAACUCCCGUCCCUGUACCUCUCCCCUCCGGGCAGGGCCGAGCCCCCCCUUCCCCGCCAAUCCGGAGCAGAUGAGGCGAGACUAAGCGGCAAGCCCACCCUGGGAAGAGGCUGGGGAGACCUAAUGGGCAGGGUCCCCCUCAUCUCCAUCACCAAGCUGAGCACUCGUGCCCAUGCCACCCCCCAGCCCCAGCCUGGGGAAAGGAGGAAAAGUGGGCACCCUAGCCCGGAGGUGGCGGGGGAGGGGGGUGUGGGGGCUGGUGUCCGAGACACCCGGCUGGGCGGGCACAGAUAGGAUCUGAACACAGGGAAGCAUGGCCUAGCUCUUUGAUCCACAGCCAGCCACGCUGGGCCUGGACCCGGAGGGAGGCACGGCUGUCUUCCGGCCCGGCUUUGCACCGCUGCCAGGGGUCCUGUGGGGCCCUCAGAGGGAGAGGCGUCCAAUACCCGGCCCUCCCCCAAAUACCCUCUAUCCCAACUGCUCUCAGAAGAGGCGUGAGCGUCUACAGUGAACCCAGCACAGAAACCUGCUAGGGGAGCUGCUGUUGACUGCAUCGCGAUCCAAAGGACCGGCGUCUUUUGUAGAUGCAGGGGCUGAGCCAGGCCAAGCGCGCCGUGGAGGCCCGCGUGGACGCAGACCCGGGUGCCAUACAGAUGCGCUGGAAUCCAGGCACUUUCCCGCGCUCCGCAAAUCUAGAUGUUUCAGCCUGGAUCGAGCGAGGGUUAGAGGGUUAGUCAGGCCAGGGUCAACUUCAGAGUCAUGGGCUCCCUAAAUGCGACUUCUAGGGUUGAGUUGCUGUGGACGAGCGACCCAUGUCGGAAUCCCGCGCCCACGUGGCUGCCCAAAGUUCCGAGUCUCCGGGCUGCAGGUUCUAGUCACGGAACCGAGUUGGGAGAGUCAUAGGGGCUGGGACUUGGAGGAUCGGCUGAGGUCCGGUGCUCUUGGCUGUGUUCGCGGCUCGGAGCCGUCGCCUGACUGAGGGGCCCGUCACAGAUGUGUGAUGUAUAAGCUCUGCACGCAACAGGAGCUCAAUAAAUGUGCGAAGGGGGGUAUACUUAUGUUCGCACUGUAUGCAGGCGGCCUAGAAGGAAGUCCCUGAUUGGCACAGGGAUGGAGGAUGGGGCAAGAGCCGCAACAGCGCCGCGGAGUUCCAACGCUGCCGGUUCCCUGGGGUACGAGCACAGCCUCAAGCAGCCUCAAGCCCUAGGAAGCCCCCAGUUCAAAGCACAGGGCGCAUUGGAGCCUGGGCACGAUACAGUUCACACCACGGCUGCGAUGGCUCUCGGGCGGGAACACGCUGCGCAGAGACUCUUCCCGGACAAACUUCCAGAGCCCCUGGAGGACGGCCUGAAGGCCCCGGAGUGCACCAGCGGCAUGUACAAAGAGACCGUCUACUCCGCCUUCAAUCUGCUCAUGCAUUACCCACCCCCCUCGGGAGCAGGGCAGCACCCCCAGCCGCAGCCCCCGCUGCACAAGGCCAAUCAGCCCCCCCACGGUGUCCCCCAACUCUCUCUCUACGAACAUUUCAACAGCCCACAUCCCACCCCUGCACCUGCGGACAUCAGCCAGAAGCAAGUUCACAGGCCUCUGCAGACCCCUGACCUCUCUGGCUUCUACUCCCUGACCUCAGGCAGCAUGGGGCAGCUCCCCCACACUGUGAGCUGGUUCACCCACCCAUCCUUGAUGCUAGGUUCUGGUGUACCUGGUCACCCAGCAGCCAUCCCCCACCCGGCCAUUGUGCCCCCCUCAGGGAAGCAGGAGCUGCAGCCCUUCGACCGCAACCUGAAGACACAAGCAGAGUCCAAGGCAGAGAAGGAGGCCAAGAAGCCAACCAUCAAGAAGCCCCUCAAUGCCUUCAUGCUGUACAUGAAGGAGAUGAGAGCCAAGGUCAUUGCAGAGUGCACACUUAAGGAGAGCGCUGCCAUCAACCAGAUCCUGGGCCGCAGGUGGCACGCGCUGUCGCGAGAAGAGCAGGCCAAGUACUAUGAGCUGGCCCGCAAGGAGAGGCAGCUGCACAUGCAGCUAUACCCAGGCUGGUCAGCGCGGGACAACUACGGGAAGAAGAAGAGGCGGUCGAGGGAAAAGCACCAAGAAUCCACCACAGACCCUGGCUCGCCUAAGAAAUGCCGUGCUCGCUUUGGCCUCAACCAGCAGACGGAUUGGUGUGGUCCGUGCAGGUGGGUUUGUCCCCACCAUCGUUCUCCCUUUGCUUUAAGCUGCUUCCCUGACUCUGCACAUGUUCCACUGGGCCUGCAGCCCACUCCUUUGGCCCCUCAGCCCACUAGCAUACUCAGCAGAUUGGGAGCCCAGGCCUCCUGAGAAUAGUAGUAAAUACUGAACACAGCGCGUGGAGAAGACCACUUGGGUCUAAGUGCAGGAGGAUUGGAGAGAAAGACACAGAAUGUUCCAGAAAGGAAGGACAGACUCAAGAAGGCAGCUCUGAUGCCAGUGGGCCUAGCAGGUCCUCAGCAAACAGACAGCUCAGCCACCACUAAGGGGGCCUGGAGCCCAUUCUACCAGGCCUCAAAGUCAUUAUGGCCCAUGGGCUCCCUCACUUCCUCUUCAAGAUGGGAUCCCUGCCUGUACCAUCCUGAGCCCUUAAUCUGAAAAAGCAAGGUGACAACAACACAGAACCAUCUGGUUGCCAGGUAGCCUUAUGACUUGCUAUCUUGUACCUACUGAUACCAAAGGGCUGGAGAGGCUGGGGGAGAGGACCCAGGGGGUACCCUGGGCUGUCUGAGGGAAAGGGCUCAUGUGUUUCACCAUACAACAGAGAAAUACUUGUGGGUGUGACAAGGUUUACCCAACAAGUGGUUAAAGUUUCCUCAGUCAGUUUCAGGCCAGGCCUGGCAGGGCUAAGAUAGAGGGUACUCCAGGCAGUAAGGCCACUGGCUCUAAGGAACACUUGUCCAGCCUCUCAGUGUACCCACCACACUCCCUGUCCAAGGGCAAGGAGGAGUUUGGGGUGUGUCUGUGUAUCCACAUACAUAUGCACGGUGGGAAACAACCCUGUCUUCAGGGGAAGUUCUAUUCCAUUCAUUCCAUCAGAGACAAACUGGCCCAGAGAACUCAAGGAUGGUAAUGGACAAGAGUCACUGUCCAUGUCUUCUUCCUCUAGCCCAGCUUGAGGACUGGGAUGGCUGGGCAAGGAAGCCAUAGGCAUUGCGGCCCCUUGCCUUGGUGCAGAUGUGAGUCCCACAAACACAUCUGGAGAAGCUCAAAGGCCGGGACUGGGAGAUGACUCCCUUGGAAGACAGGAGAGAUGACUCCCUUGGAAGACAGAUGACAGCCCAUAGGCCUAGUGACAAAAGGCCCCUUUGCCACCUUGUGGCUGUUCUGGGAACUGCACCUGUCCUAGGUCUGGGCCAGACCAAGCAGAAUGGCAGUCUGAGGACACUGACUUACCACCCAAGUCCCAGGAAGAGAGGACAAGGAAUCAGCCAGGCCUGUGCAAAGGCAGCAUUUUUUGGUUGUGGUGUAUGACUAUGAAUUCACCCUCUGUUUACAGAUAACUCUCUUCACUAUUCCUAGGAGGAAAAAGAAAUGCAUUCGGUACUUACCCGGAGAAGGCCGCUGCCCCAGCCCCGUUCCUUCCGAUGACAGUGCUCUAGGCUGCCCCGGGUCCCCAGCUCCCCAGGACUCACCCUCAUACCAUCUGCUGCCCCGCUUCCCCACAGAACUGCUUACUAGCCCUGCGGAGCCGGCACCUACAUCCCCAGGUCUCUCCACUGCUCUCAGCCUCCCAACCCCAGGGCCCCCACAGGCCCCCCGCAGCACCCUGCAGAGCACACAGGUACAGCAACAGGAAUCUCAGAGACAGGUGGCCUAGCAGGCACAGGACACCUGGCCGCCUCCAGGAGCCUACCCCCUGAAAGUGACAGAGACCCAGAUCUCAUGGAAACUGGCCAGGGGUCCUGUUAACGUCAUCUCAGGGUCCAGACCCUGAAGAUUUCAGAGGCUGCAGGACUUCUGCCUGAACCUGGGGUCAUCGAUUCAAACUGCUCCAAGUGGUGGGAAUCAGAUCUGUCUUGAUGUGUCAUCUAAUUAAGGGAAUCCCUUGUACCUAUGGCUGCCUGCAUCUAUUCUUUGUACCAUCUGUCUUGCCAGCCAGAAGCCUCUGCCUCCCUAGCUUUUCUGCUAUAGGUCAGAGAUGGGCUGAACUGAGCCUAGCUACCUUCUCUACCCAUCUCCCCCAUCCCCCACUGCCACACCCUCCCCAUUCAGACACUUCAUGGACCAAGAAUGAGCUGGUUUGUCAAACAACAUGUGAGCAUGGUCACAAGCACAAAGCUCAAGAUGACAGCUCUUCUAAGGAAAUGGAGAAGCUCUGUUUAUAAAAACAAAAACAAAACCAGCUGCUACUCAUAAGUUGGACCAGAGGAAGCCCCUUACUAUGAUCUCAGGAGCUUGCAAGAAGCAGGAAGGGGAAUGGAAUAGGUUAAGUUUAGGCCUAUCAACCUAAGCAACAGAAAUAAUCUGACACUACCUUAUCAGGCAAAUUGGGGAGGGGAGGGUGUAUCUAGCUCUAGUUCAAAUUAUUUGGAAGUGUUCCCUGAGAAACCCACCAGCCUAAGAAGCUCUGGCCCCAGGCUUGUCACUAGCAGCUGCAGUCAACAGUUCAAAGAAGUCAUGGCCCAAAUCCAGUGUGCACCCCUCCCCAUUCACAGAGCCUUUUUCACAAUUCCAUUUCCAGUUCAUCUAUGGCAGUCCAGCCAGCUCCUGGGCAGCUUGAGAGGGCAAACCCAAAACCUCAUGACAGCCAGAGCCUGUCUUUCAGCAUUCAGUCCGCCUGGCCGGCUCCAGUUUCCCCAUGGGGCUGCGGGACAGAGGACCAUUACAACUAGAUCAAGGAGCCCAGAAAACCUCCAGUAGUGGACAACAGGUUUUCACCAUAGCCUACGUUAACCCAUUUUUGAGCCAAGCUUCAACCCUCAGCCUUGAAAAACAAGUCUUUAAUUUAAUUUUUGUUUUUUGCCUAAAUCCAAAGAAAAAGGGCUGCCGGGCCAGGCGCGGUGGCUCACGCCUGUAAUCCCAGCACUUUGGCAGGCCGAGGCAGGUGGAUCACCUGACGUCAGUAGUUUGAGACCAGCCUGGCCAACAUGGUGAAACCCUGUAUCUACUAAAAAUACAAAAAUUAGCCGGACGUGGUGGUGCGCGCAUGUAAUCCCAGCUACUCGGGAGGCUGAGGCGGAAGAAUCACUUGAACCCGGGAGGCGGAGGUUCCAGUGAGCCGAGAUGGCGCUAUUGCACUCCAGUCUGGGUAACAGGGAGACUGCAUCUCAAAAAAAAAAAAAAAAAAAAAAAAGGGCUGUCCAUGUAUUCACACACCCCUCAAAAAAAGCCUUUAGUUCCUACUUUAGCCACUGGUUUCUCAGAAUCCAAAGAUCACAUAUUCUAGUGUAACACUGCAAGAAGUCUUGAGAAAAAGAUUAUUGUAGUGUUCAAAAUAUUUUUGUAUUGUUAAUGCAUCAUCAUAGAAAAACUUUUAAACAUGAGAAUAAAGAUACUUUUUACUGGG